AGUGCUGACUCCGUACACGCGCGCUGCGGCAUGGCGGCCCACCGCCCCGGCCCGCUCAAGCAGCAGAAUAAAGCUCAUAAAGGCGGACGGCAUCGGGGUCGGGGAUCUGCACAGCGGGACGGCAAGGGCCGUCUGGCACUGAAAACCCUAAGCAAGAAGGUGAGAAAAGAACUCAGCAGAGUCGACCAGAGGCAUCGCGCCAGCCAGCUCCGAAAGCAGAAGAAGGAGGCGGUUCUGGCAGAGAAGAGACAGCUGGGUGGCAAGGAUGGCCCUCCUCAUCAGGUACUGGUGGUGCCCCUGCACAGCAGAAUUUCCCUGCCAGAGGCCAUGCAGCUGCUUCAAGAUAGGGACACUGGAACAGUACACUUGAAUGAAUUGGGAAACACCCAGAACUUUAUGCUGCUGUGCCCCCGCUUGAAACAUCGGUGGUUUUUCACCUCAGCAAGGCCAGGGGAUCUGCACGUUGUGUUAGACAUGGCUAAAGUAGCUGAUACCAUCCUGUUCCUCCUUGAUCCACUAGAAGGCUGGGACAGCACCGGUGAUUACUGUCUUUCCUGCCUCUUUGCUCAGGGCCUUCCGACCUAUACACUAGCUGUCCAGGGGAUUUCUGGCCUCCCACUGAAGAAACAAAUAGAUACCAGGAAGAAGCUAAGUAAAGCAGUGGAGAAGCGCUUUCCGCAUGACAAACUCCUCUUGUUAGACACUCAACAGGAGGCAGGGAUGCUGCUUAGGCAGUUGGCUAACCAGAAGCAACAGCAUCUUGCUUUUCGAGAUCGGCGGGCCUACCUAUUUGCCCAUGCUGUUGAUUUUGUUCCUAGUGAAGAGAAUAACUUGGUGGGCACCUUGAAAAUUUCAGGCUAUGUUCGAGGGCAGACUCUGAAUGUCAAUAGGUUGCUGCAUAUCGUUGGAUAUGGUGAUUUCCAGAUGAAACAGAUAGAUGCCCCCGGAGACCCUUUCCCUUUAAAUCCUAGAGGAAUUAAACCCCAAAAGGACCCAGACAUGGCAAUGGAGAUUUGUGCUACGGAUGCUGUAGAUGAUAUGGAAGAAGGUCUUAAAGUCCUAAUGAAGGCAGACCCUGGUAGACAGGAAUCCUUGCAAGCAGAGGUUAUCCCAGAUCCAAUGGAGGGAGAGCAAACCUGGCCCACUGAGGAGGAGCUGAGCGAGGCAAAGGAUUUCUUGAAGGAAAGUUCUAAGGUGGUAAAGAAGGUCCCCAAAGGAACAUCCAGUUACCAAGCUGAAUGGAUUUUGGAUGGUGGCAGCCAAAGUGGUGGGGAAGGAGAUGAAUAUGAAUAUGAUGAUAUGGAACAUGAGGAUUUUAUGGAGGAGGAAUCUCAGGAUGAGAGUAGUGAAGAAGAGGAAGAAUAUGAAACUAUGACUAUUGGGGAGUCUGUGCAUGAUGAUCUGUAUGAUAAGAAAGUAGAUGAAGAAGCUGAGGCAAAAAUGUUGGAGAAAUAUAAACAAGAAAGACUGGAAGAGAUGUUUCCAGAUGAAGUGGACACGCCCCGUGAUGUGGCUGCUCGAAUUCGAUUUCAGAAAUACAGAGGCCUUAAGAGCUUCCGGACAUCUCCAUGGGAUCCUAAGGAAAACCUUCCUCAAGAUUAUGCUCGAAUAUUUCAGUUUCAGAACUUUACUAACACUAGGAAAAGCAUCUUUAAAGAGGUUGAAGAAAAAGAGGUUGAAGGAGCUGAGGUUGGCUGGUAUGUCACACUUCAUGUCUCUGAAGUCCCCGUCUCAGUGGUCGAGUGCUUCAGGCAAGGAACACCCUUGAUUGCAUUUUCUUUACUACCUCAUGAACAGAAGAUGUCAGUAUUGAAUAUGGUGGUGAGGCGUGACCCUGGCAACACUGAACCUGUGAAAGCCAAGGAAGAGCUCAUAUUUCACUGUGGAUUCAGGCGCUUCCGAGCCUCACCUUUAUUCUCUCAGCACACUGCAGCGGACAAACAUAAAUUGCAGAGAUUCCUGACUGCUGACAUGGCCCUGGUGGCGACAGUCUAUGCGCCAAUCACUUUUCCUCCUGCAUCUGUGCUGCUUUUCAAGCAAAAAAGCAAUGGAAUGCACAGCCUCAUUGCUACAGGCCAUCUUAUGUCAGUAGAUCCAGACAGAAUGGUCAUCAAGAGAGUUGUUCUGAGUGGUCAUCCUUUCAAAAUUUUUACUAAGAUGGCAGUAGUACGUUACAUGUUCUUCAACAGAGAGGAUGUGCUGUGGUUUAAACCAGUGGAACUGAGAACGAAGUGGGGCCGGAGAGGACAUAUCAAGGAACCUUUAGGUACCCAUGGCCACAUGAAAUGCAGCUUUGAUGGGAAGCUAAAAUCUCAAGACACAGUACUGAUGAACCUGUAUAAACGAGUCUUCCCCAAAUGGACUUAUGAUCCAUAUGUACCAGAACCAGUACCCUGGCUGAAAAGUGAGAUUUCUUCAACAGUGCCUCAAGGGGGCAUGGAGUAAUGGAUUCAAAGAGAUUCUGUCUUACCGGUGCCAGUCAGUACUCCAGGGAUGGGAGGCACAAGUUGUGAUUGGGCAAAGUUUAUUUUCUAUGUCAGCCUGUCAGUCCACUGCCCCAUUUUGCAAGACUUUUUUUUAGCCUUGACAAAAUGUCUCAGUUAAGUAUAAAAGUUUUUCCACUACUUAGUCCAAAAAAAACUAUUAAAUCUUAAUGAAAUAGCCACUCUCCAUUAAGAAUCUGAUAACUAAGAGUUGACAAUACUAGGAAACAAAAUGUCUUCAGUAUCUAAAGACACUGAAUUCCCACCAUUUCCUUUUCUGUAAAUUAAACAGAAACAGACUGAUAAGAAGCUGGCCUUUCAGCCUGCUUCACCCAAGUUAUGGAGGAGGUUAAGUCUACAUUUCCACCACUGAGCACAAUACAAAUGUUCUUUACUUCUGGGGAAACAGUUUGAAAAUGUUGAGACAGCACAGCAGCCACUCCAACACCAGCUGUAGGUUCAAUGAGUAGUUUCAUCCUCUCCCACACCAGCUGGGUUGCACACUGUUGAUAUGGAAGGGAGUAGGAAUUAGUGAAAGGGGAGUCUAGUUGGUUUACCUAUAAAGUUCAGAUGAGAAUACGUGUCCAGUUUGAAUUUUCUUAUCACUGUGUACACACGCUUCCCAAAGCUUUUCUUUAAUUCUGACUCUGCUUCUGUCAAGAGGGUUGUCAUUAAUACAUCUAGGGUACCCUCCCAUGUCAUGAAGUUACCUAGUCAGGUUCCCGUGGGUCACUUGCUACUCCUAAGGGAAGUUUCUUCUGCCUAAGAAGUUACACCAUGCUUUGCUAUUUCUUUUCUUGCUGGAGCCUCACCUUAAUUUCAUCCUCUGUGACAGUGAAGAUAUCAUCCACAAGGUCCCUGAUAAUAGGCCAGGUGUUCAAGCCAAUGCUGGAUUUGACACCAUCUGCUAUGGUUUCUGGAGGAUAAAGAUUGGGCAUCAGUUUCCCCUUCAGCUUGGACUGGUAGCAGUCAUCUGCAUUUGAGGGUUCAGCAGCAUAUACCUUCACACUAGGUUUCAGAGCCUGGGAAGAGGAAUAUUAAGACAUCUUAACAACAAACCACAACAUUGCCUGCAUGUCUAAAAGAAAAUAUGGGCCUGGUGUGGUGGCUCACACCUGUAAUCCCAACACUUUGGGAGCCCGAGGCGGGUGGAUCAGCUGAGGUCAGGAGUUCAAGACCAGCCUGGCCAACCUGGUGAAAUGCAGUGUCAACUAAAAAUAGGAAAAUCAGCCAGGCGUGGUGGCAGACCCCUGUAAUCCCAGCUACUCAAGAGGCUGAGGUAGGAGAAUCACUUGAACUUGGGAGGGGUAGGUUGCAGUGAGCUGAGAUCACACCAAAAUGGGGUGGGGCGCAGUGGCUCACGCCUGUAAUCCCAGCACUUUGGGAGGCCGAGGUGGGCGGAUCACGAGGUAGGGAGAUCAAGACCAUCCUGGCUAACACGGUGAAACCCCGUCUCUACUAAAAAUACAAAAAAAAAAAACAAAAAAAAACUAGCCAGGCAUGGUGGCAGGCACCUGUAGUCCCAGCUACUCGGGAGGCAGAGGCAGGAGAAUGGCGUGAACCUGGGAGGUGGAGCUUGCAGUGAGCCAAGAUCGUGCCACUGCACUCCAGCCUGGGUGACAGAGUGAGACUCCGUCUCAAAAAAAAAAAGAAAAUAGGCACAAUAAGUAAUACAUUUCUGCCCAAGUAAGAGCCUUCCCUUUUGUGGAUGUAAUGAAAAUAUCUUCAAGCACUUUAUAAAUAAAUUAUAUGUCUGAUACUA